GCGGCCGCCCGCGGUCCAGCUCCGACAACAGGAAUUUUCUCCGAGAGCGGGCCGGGCUCAGUUCAGCUGCUGUCCAGACCCGGAUCGGCAACAGUGCCGCCUCCAGACGUUCUCCUGCCGCUCGCCCGCCCGUCCCAGCGCCCCCAGCCCUCCCGCGAGGGCGCCCCGGGACGGAAGGAUCCACCAGUCUGUCGGCGCCCGCCGUUCUCGUGGUCGCCGUCGCCGUCGUCGUGGUGGUAGUCUCCGCCGUCGCCUGGGCCAUGGCCAAUUACAUCCACGUCCCUCCCGGCUCCCCGGAGGUGCCCAAGCUGAACGUCACCGUUCAGGAUCAGGAGGAGCAUCGCUGCCGGGAGGGGGCCCUGAGCCUCCUGCAACACCUGCGGCCUCACUGGGACCCCCAGGAGGUGACCCUGCAGCUCUUCACAGAUGGAAUCACAAAUAAACUUAUUGGCUGUUACGUGGGAAACACCAUGGAGGAUGUAGUCCUGGUGAGAAUUUAUGGCAAUAAGACUGAGUUAUUAGUCGAUCGAGAUGAGGAAGUAAAGAGUUUUCGAGUGUUGCAGGCUCAUGGGUGUGCACCACAACUCUACUGUACCUUCAAUAAUGGACUAUGCUAUGAAUUUAUACAAGGAGAAGCACUGGAUCCAAAGCAUGUCUGCAACCCAGCCAUUUUCAGGCUAAUAGCUCGUCAGCUUGCUAAAAUCCAUGCUAUUCAUGCACACAAUGGCUGGAUCCCCAAAUCUAAUCUUUGGCUAAAGAUGGGAAAGUAUUUCUCUCUCAUUCCCACAGGAUUUGCAGAUGAAGACAUUAAUAAAAGGUUCCUAAGUGAUAUCCCAAGCUCUCAGAUUCUCCAGGAAGAGAUGACUUGGAUGAAGGAGAUUCUUUCCAACCUGGGCUCACCUGUUGUGCUUUGCCAUAAUGACCUAUUGUGUAAGAAUAUAAUCUACAAUGAGAAACAAGGUGAUGUACAGUUCAUUGAUUAUGAAUAUUCUGGAUACAACUACCUGGCAUAUGAUAUUGGAAAUCAUUUCAAUGAAUUUGCAGGUGUGAGUGAUGUAGACUAUAGUCUGUAUCCAGAUAGAGAACUACAGAGUCAGUGGCUGCGUGCUUACCUUGAAGCCUACAAAGAAUUUAAGGGCUUUGGGACUGAAGUUACUGAAAAGGAGGUAGAAAUACUCUUCAUUCAAGUCAAUCAGUUUGCAUUGACACUGCAAUCUGCCUUUUCCCUCACUGCUGUAAAAAGAAAAUCAGGUAAGGCUUACCAAUCAUGACAUAAUUGCCAAGUCCAAUGUAAAUUUUUCAGUCCUUAUCUUACUUGAUCUGUCAGUAGCAUUUGACAGUAUUUACCAUUGAUUUAAAAAAUGUUCUCUUGUUGACUUUUGUGAUAGUUUUAUGUAUGGUGAAAAUAAGGAAAUGAUCAAAGUCUGGUUUCAUGAAUUACACACUUUAUUGCCAUACAAAGAUAGUUUUUUCCCCUUAGGUUCACAAUGCUUAAAGAGAGGAAGAACAACCUGAACAAAUCUCACAGGGAAUAUACUCAAUAGAUGAGGUACAUUAACUAUAUAAUGAGUGAGUUCCAAAUUGUUAAAAGUCUAGUCCAAUUCGGAUGAAAGCAGGAGAGGAUUGAGCUUUUUACGAUUAGUUUCUUGGGCUUGACCAACAUAGGAGAGAUCCAUGAAGACACUUGAAGUUCCUGGACACAAGAAGUUGGACGUUAAUGUUGUCAUGACAAGACUUCAAAGCUCCAAGGCCUGUAGAGGCCUGAACUCUGCUUUUGGAGAAGUAACUGACAGAGUGUAGCCUGUCACAGACUAAGUGUUCAGAAUGUCAAACUGUUAUGUUUAUAUGUAUUUUGAAGUCCACUAGUUAAGGUCAGUUACUCACAUGGGGUCUGAGAAAGUGUAAUGUAACAUUCCCAAGAGGGGAAGGAGUUCACCCCAAGUACUCACAUAUGGAGUUUGUAUUGGCAUUCUCCAGAGGGACAGAACUAAUGGGAUAUAUGUAUAAGUGGAAGGAAGUUUAUUAGGGAGAAUUGGCUCACCUGAUCACAAGUUGAAGUCUCACAGUAGGCCGUCUGCACGCUGAGGAAGAAAGAAGCCAGUAGUGGCGCAGUACAAGUUUGAAAGUCUCAAAACCAGAAGAGCCGACAGUGCUGCCUUCAGUCUGUGGCCAAAGGCCCAAGAGCCCCCUGGCAAACCACUGGCGUUUAAGUCCAAGUGUCCAAAUGCUGAAGAACUUGGAUUCUGAAGUCCAAGGGCAGGAGGAAGCAUCCAACAUGGGGAAAAAGAAGGAAGCCAGAAAACCCAGCAAGCAAAGUUAUCCUACCUUCUUCUGCCUGCUUUGUUUUUGCCGUGCUGGCAGCCAAUUGGAUGAUACCAGCCGACAUUGAGGGUGGGUCUUCCUCUCCCAGUCCACAGACUCAAAUGUCAGUCUCCUCUGGCAACACCCUCACAGACACACCCAGAAACAAUACUUUCCUAGCCAACUAGGCAACCCUCGAUCCAAUCAAGUUGACACCUAACAUUAACCAUCAUAGGGUCCGAUAAGACUUCGCAUUCUCCUAGGGAGUGGGAGUAGUUGCAUUUUACAUAUGCGAUCUGAUAGUUCUCAUAUUCGUGUUUUUUGUUCUUGGUUUUUUGUUUUUUUUUUUUUUUUGAUAUGGAGUCUCACUCUAUCGCCCAGCCUUGAGUGCAGUGGCACAAUCUUGGCUCACUGCAACCUCUGCCUCCUGGAUUCAAGCAGUUCUCUGGCCUCAGUAGCUAGGAGUACAGGCGUUUGCCGCCACACCCAGCUAAUUUUUGUAUUUUUGGUAAAGACGGGGUUUCACCAUAUCGGCUAGGCUGGUUUCGAACUCCUGACCUCAAAUGAUCCACCCACCUCGGCCUCCCCGAGUGUUGGGAUUACAGGUGUGAGCCACCUCACCUGGCCAUAUUCUUGAAGGGUGGAGGAAUACAUACAUCAUUUUAAAGCUGUGUGACAAAUUCUCUUUUUGUACUGUCUUGCUCAGUCUCUUAAUCUGGCUCCUCUUUCCUCCUCUUCUCCCAGCCCUCUUACAUGUUAACAGUAUUCCCUAGUGUUCUGAUUUGGGUCUACCCCUUCCAAGUUCUGUUCUUGGUUCCUAAAAUGUUCUUGAUUUCAGCACCUUCUCCUUUUAUUUUUUACCUUUGAUUGAGGACUGAAUCUCUUGCCAACAUUAGCCUUUACUGGUCUCUUUGCCUUCAGUUUUUUUUGUUGUUGUUUUGUUUUUCCUGUCUUUCAUUUAUUCUGUAUAUUAAAAAAGUGAUCCUUUCUAGUAAUUAGAAUUUAAUUAAUUAGAUUGUGUCACUUUUCUAUUUUAUGGCUCCCUGUGACCUACAGAAUGAAAUCCAAAUGACAGCAUCUGCAAACUCUUAUUUCCCACUACUUCACACGUCCUACUUCUGCUCUAGCAGAGUCAUUUUGUGCGGGCAUACUCCAUGAUGUUGCAUGUCUGUGUACUUAGAAGCUUAUUCCUUCUACCUGGAAUGCCUUUUACCCUGCAUCUCUUGGCAGAUUUCUCUUAUUCCUUAUGGAUGUGUCUUAAGUGCUGUUUCCUCCUUAGAUAGUUUAUGAAGCUGCUUUGAUAAAAAGAAAAGCAGGUCUGAAUGAUAAGAUCAGGGUAUACAUGUUUUGAAAUAGUAUAAAUGGUUAGUAAAUGUUGAUUGCUCAGGCCAUGAUACAGACUUCUAAAGAUUAUAACAUUUCACUUGUCAUUGAUUGUUUAAUGUUGAGAUGGUGGCAAACAAAAGUAGGUAUAUGGGUUAUAAAACCAAACAGAGUAUACGUAAUGGCUUUGUGGAGCUUUUCUUCCCCCGCCCCCCCCUCCAUUAUAUGCACACUGGGGAUUUAUUUUAGUUAUUUAUUUACCAUAUAAAGCUUUGAAUAUUUCUUUGCAACAGGGGUAAGUAGUCUAGAAAUUAAAAUACCCUUUAACAGAGAGACUUACAUAUCCAUAACUUCCAAAUGUGAAAGAGAUAGUAUAGUUACAGAAUUUAUUAUUUUUUUGGAUGUACUUGUAUUUUGGGGGGAUGCAAAUGAUGAAUGGGCUGUUUUCUGCCUUUGUUUCUCAUCCAUUUAGAAUCUACUGUUAUAUAUUAAUUUAUCACUUUUCCCCCUAUAAAAAUGGUUGCCUACACAAAUGAGAUUUCAGUGAGGUUUUAUGGAUAAUGCUUCUCUAGUGUAGAAUCGUUUAGUUAAUUUAUAUAAGUAUAUGAAUAAAAACUGAUUGAGAAAUAUAGUUACCAUCUCUGCUUGACAAUGGUGAGAAGAGCUAAGUUGGUAUGUUUUUAAAAUGCAGAAUGACUCUUGAUUUCUCAGUCUUUUCCACUACAGAGCAAAUUUAGUAGGAAGAAGAGAUUAGGAUACCAUCUAUAGGUGAUUUUAUAUCAGCGUAAAAUAUGCAAGGCAAUUUAGACUAGUGGUUCUCAAAUUUUUCAAUCUUAGGACCCCUUCAUACUUAAAAUGUUUUUGAAGACCUCUACAAGCUUUUGUUUUUGUGAAAUAAUUAACAGUAUUUAACAUAUUAGAAGUCAAAAUUCAAACAUUUAAGUAUAUAUAUAUAUUUAAAAUAAACUCAUUACAUUAACGCAAAUGCCAUAAAUAGAAUACUAUUUUUCAAAACAAAAAACAAUUUAGUGAGAAGACUGGCAUUAUUUUACACUUCUGCAAAUUUCUUUAAUGUCUGGUUUAAUGGAAUACAGCAGGAUUCCCGUAUCUGCUUCUGCAUUACAUCUUUUGUGAUGGAUUGUUUCAUUUCAAGUAUAUGAAAAAAAGUUUCACACAUGCAUGUUGGAAAAGAGGAGUAUUUUGCCUUUUCAGAUAAUUGUGGAUAUUCUUUUUUGAUACUAGACCAAAGCUCAACAAGUGAUAGUUUCUUAAAGGUUAGUUGCCAUGAAUAAUCUGAAUGUAUCAAUUAAUUUUUUACUCUAUUACAUUAAAAUCUACUGGUUUAUCUUGCAGAUUGAAUGAUUCUUUUACCUGUAUGUGAUUUUGUAAUUUUAACUUAUUAGUUAUUUGGAAAAUAAUUGAUUCAUUGAGUUGUAUAGAUCUUCCAAAUGUUGACACAUCUCAUUAUAAGAUAGCUAAAGAUCACAUAUGUUGAUAUCACCACCAGUGUCAUCAGAAAAACUUAUAGUACUAUAUUGAGAAGCUGUUAAGCUCACAGAAUCACAUAAAACUUUUCUCAUGUUCUAAUUUUAGGGUGAAAACUUGAAUUUUAUCAUUGGCAACAAAUAUUGUCAGUUAUUUUCACUGAAAUGGCAAGUUAUCUUUUUUAUAGUUGAGAAAAUGUCUGCCAAAUACUCAAGUCUGAUAACUCUAGUUUGAUAACUCUAGUUUGUAUAUUAGUCAUUUUUUUCAAGUAAAAAUUGUGUCCCAUUAAAAAUGUGCAAAUUCAACUCAAAAGUCAGUUACCUAGGUGUUUUUCCUGAGACAUCCAUUGUACUUUGGAUAUGCAGUAGACGUGCUUUAUAUGUACUGCCUAUUUCCUCCCACAGAAUACUAGAGCACGUACUCCAGGGUAGAGAUUUAAUAAAAUUAAUAGUUUUAAUGGCUUCACAAAGGACAUUCUUUAGUGACAUUGGCUUUUUACUGUUAUUGUGUGAUGGUGAAGAAUAAGACUAUUACACUAGUGUGAUUUGCUACCACUGCCUUGACUUAAGGUAACAGUAGUUUCACCCUCACUGCUUUUGAACCAUUGGUGCAAAUGUUAACAUAGUCAAAAAGGCAAGUAACAUAUCAGUAUAAUUAUGAAAGUAAUUUUGGGCCUCCGAAAACUCCCAUGGGUUCAUCGACCACUUUAAGAACCUCUGAUGUAGACUUUGAAAAGAAGGAAGUCCUCUAAUUUCAUAAUUUCAUUUCUCAAUACCUGAUAUACUUUUUUAGAUAGAAGACCAUUUUUGAAAAUCUUUAUCAUUUUUAAUCAUUCUGGUUUCAUAUAGUAAGAAUAGCUAGCAUUCUAUUGAAUAUUUGUUAUAUGCCAGCUAUAGGUACUAUUAUGACCUACAUUUUACAGAUGAGGAAAUAAACGCACCACGUGAAGUGCUUAAAGCCACACGCCAGAGCCCAGCUUGUUUUUUUAACUUUUAUGCUUCAUGUGCAAGUGACUUUAGUUGUUUAGUCUUUGCUACAUUGUUUAUUCUUUUCUAUCUCUAUAUCAGGAAAGAAAUUAUAUUCCUGUUCUUUUUUUUUUUUUAAGAGACAGUGUCUCACUGUGUUGCCCAAGCUGGAGUGCAGUGGCAUGCUCCUCACUGCAGCCUUGAACUCCUGAGCUCUAGUGAUCACCAGCCUCCUGAAUAGCUGAAUAGUUAGUGGUAUUUUUUUGAGGAAGCCAAAAACAAAGUGCAGAGUGCUUUUUAAAUAGAGAUCUUUAGGUUGAAAAAUUUUUUUUACAUGUAUUAUAUCCUUUAGUCUUUAAAACAAUCCUGUGUAGAAUACAGAAUGGCUAAUAUUCCCAUCUCGUAAAUGAUAGAUCUGACACUAAAGUUUGUGACUUAUUAAAGGUUGCAAAGGUACUCAGAGAUAGAGCCUGGACUGGAACCUCUACAUCUUGUAAUUCAAAUUAAGAAUUCUUUUUGGUAUACUGUGCUGCUUGGUAUUUUUAAAUACCAAGGUCAUGGCUGUUGAAUACUUUUUUGUUAGAGCCCCUUUGUUACUGUUGCUGUAAUGAAUUUAGCUGAAACAAAAACCUUGUCUUUAAUACUGUUUCUACUUAGAAUAUUUCUAGUUAGAAUAUAGUAUUUCUUGGGAAGUGAAAUCUUGUUCAGAUUUUAAAAUAUUACCCUGUUUAACUGAAAAUAGAUUGUAAAGCACACAUAAUUAUUUUACAGUUACUAAUUACAUGCUAAUUUCCCUGUAAGUCCAAAACCCAUAUUUUUCCUGACAUAAGUUGUGUUACUUUAUGUUGUGGUCUGUUAUGCAGAAUUAAGCCAGUAAGAUCAUUUUCAGAUGUUUGUCACCCCUAGAACAUUUUUCACAUUUAAAUAUAUUUAUUGCUUGUGAGAUUUGGAUUUUCUUUUGUGUUUAUAUUUGUAUGUCAAGAAACAAAGGCCUUUGAUAUAAUAAUGUGUAAGCCUGUUAGCAAUUAUAACCAUUAAAAACACUAACAUCUAUCAGUGCUGAUGGUAAACUUUGCUUUAUAAAAAAGCACAUCACAGGAACUGGCCUCUAUUUUUCAAGUGAUUAUAAUUUACCAUAAUCUCCUUUGGUGUUGACGAAAGUGAUCUGUAGCCAUCUAGUGGGUGCAGACGUCAGUAGGAUCUAGGUUUUAGACGCUUUAUAUAAAAAGAACAGCAAGAAAGUGUGGUGCAUGGAGUUGAUUUAGAGGAUAGAAUUAGCAAUUCAUAUGUGUUUUACAGAGAAAUUCAUUAUCAUAAUUUUUGAUUUUUCUUUCCUU